CAAAAUCAUCUCAGAGCUGUCUGUGAGCGCAUCAGUAAUUAGAAUACAAUUGACCCUCGAGCAACACAGAGUCGACUGCGUGAGAUUUGCUUUCACCUCUGCCACCCCUGAAUCAGCAAGACCAACCCCUCCUCUUCCUCUUCCUCCUCAGCCUACUCAAGGCUCCUUUUCGCCCUCUGCCGGCGGACAGUGGCAGAACCCAGCUUUCUGGUUGCUAUGGGUACCGAGGUAACGCGGUAACCAAGGAGACCAAGACGGAAACUCCCGGCAGCUAUCCGCGGCCAUCCGGCGGUGGUGACGCGAGAGGCUGGGGUCUCCAGCCUUUAGUCUGCCUGCGCGUUCACAUGCACCCACUUACUUCUUGAAGUCUACUCCUCACAAGUAAGGGCUAUGGUGCGGGGUGCCCGAUUCCUGAGAAAUCUGAAGAUGUGGAAGUUUAUUUUUUCUUCCCAAAAUCAGCAGUAGAGGGACUCAGGACCAACUCCUCUUCAUCUUCGUCUUCCUCAGCCUGCUCAAUGUGAAGCCCCUGAUCAUGAUUCACUUCCACUUAAUAAAUAAAGUGUUUACAAAUCAGAAUAACUUUUAGACAAUAUUAAGGUGGUAAUCAUGAACAGAAAAGAUUUUGUAGUUCUUCCAUGGGGAAAACCUGGAAAUUCUGUAAAGCUAAAAUAUAGAAAUGCUCAAGAACUGCGAAUGGAGAAAGUACAGUUAGAGUUUGAGAACCAAGAGAUGGAGAAGAAACUGCAAGAAUUCCGAUCCACAAGAAACAAAGAAAAGGAAGAUAGAGAGUCAAGCGAGUAUUACUGGAAAUCUGGAAAAGUGGGCAAAUUGGUCAAUCAAUCAUAUAUGAUGUCACAAAAUAAAGGAAAUGUUGUUAAGUUUUCUGCUGGAAAAGUGAAAUUAAAAUUGCUGAAGGAACAGAUUCAAGAGCCAGUGAAACCAACAGUUAAUUAUAAAAUGGCAAAUUCUUCAGAAUGUGAAAAACCCAAGAUAAAUGGGAAAGUAUGUGGACAGUGUGAGAACAAAGCUGCUCUACUGGUAUGCCUUGAAUGUGGAGAAGAUUAUUGUUCAGGAUGCUUUGCUAAAGUUCACCAGAAAGGGGCACUAAAGCUCCACAGAACAACUCUUUUGCAGGCAAAAUCUCAAAUAUUAUUCAAUGUAUUGGAUGUUGCCCAUCAGUUUAUAAAGGAUGUUAAUCCAGAUGAACCCAAAGAGGAGAAUAAUUCUACAAAGGAAACCAGUAAAAUUCAACAUAAACCCAAAUCUGUACUUCUCCAGAGGAGCAGCUCUGAGGUAGAAAUUACAACGAUGAAAAGAGCACAACGUACAAAACCAAGAAAGAGUCUGUUGUGUGAAGGGUCAUUCGAUGAAGAAGCUUCUGCACAGUCCUUUCAGGAAGUGUUAAGUCAAUGGAGAACCGGAAAUCAUGAUGACAACAAGAAACAGAAUUUACAUGCAGCAGUAAAAGACUCAUUGGAAGAAUGCGAAGUACAGACUAAUCUGAAAAUUUGGAGAGAACCACUUAAUAUUGAACUUAAAGAAGACAUUCUAUCCUAUAUGGAAAAAUUAUGGCUUAAAAAACACAGGAGAACUCCACAAGAGCAACUUUUUAAAAUGCUACCAGAUACGUUCCCACAUCCACAUGAAACCACUGGUGAUGCACAGUGUUCUCAAAAUGAAAACGAUGAAGAUAGUGAUGGUGAGGAGACCAAAGUACAACACACAGCUCUUUUAUUGCCAGUAGAAACAUUAAACAUAGAGAGACCUGAACCAUCUCUAAAGAUAGUCGAACUGGAUGAUACUUAUGAAGAGGAAUUUGAAGAAGCAGAAAAUAUUGUGCCUUACAAAGUUAAAUUAGCUGAUGCAGACAGUCAACGAAGUUGUGCUUUUCAUGAUUGUCAGAAGAAUAGCUUUCCAUAUGAAAAUGGCAUCCAUCAACAUCAUGUUUUCGAUAAGGGAAAGAGAGACUUCUUAAAUCUUUGUCUGAGAAACAGCUCUACUUAUUAUAAAGAUAAUUCAAAAGCAGAAACUUCAAACACAGAUUUUGACAACAUCGUGGAUCCUGAUGUGUAUUCUUCUGACAUUGAAAAAAUUGAGGAAAGCACCUCCUUUGAAAGAAAUUUAAAGGAGAAAAAUAUAGGUUUAGAAAGUAAUCAAAAGUCUGAUGAUUCCUGUGUAUCACUUGAAAGCAAGGACACUUUGCUAGGUAGAGAUUUAGAAAAAGCUCCCAUUGAGGAGAAAUUAUCUCAAGACAUCAAAGAAUCCUUGGAAUUGAGCAAUCUGUAUAAGAGGCCAAGCUUUGAAGAAUCAAAAACUACAAAGUCAUCACUGUUGUUACAAGAAAUAGCCUGCAGAAGUAAGCCUAUAACAAAACAAUAUCAAGGACUUGAGAGAUUCUUUAUUUUUGAUACAAAUGAAAGACUCAACUUACUUCCUUCUCAUCGUUUAGAAUGCAACAAUUCCAGUACUAGGAUUACACUUGCAGGUCAGAAAUCACAGAGACCUUCAACAGCAAAUUUUCCACUUUCCAACUCUGUUAAAGAAAGCUCCAGUUGCCUUUCAUCCUCUCAUCCUCGAUCAAGAAGUGCAGCUGCUCAAUCAUCAUCUAGAGCUGCUUCUGAAAUUUCAGAAAUUGAAUAUAUUGAUAUUACUGACCAGAAUGAGCUUUCCUUAGAUGACACUACUGAUCAACAUACUUUAGACAAUUUGGAAAAAGAAUUACAAGUGCUGAGAUCUCUUGCAGAUACUUCAGAAAAGCUUUACAGCUUAACCUCAGAAGAGUUCCCAGAUUUCAGCAGCCAAUCACUGAAUAUAAGUCAGAUUUCCACAGAUUUCCUUAAGACCUCACAUGUGAGGGGUCCCUGUGGAGUUGAGGAAUUGAGCUGUUCUGGAAGAGAUACCAAAAUUCAGUCUUUGCUGUCACUUUCUGAGAGCAGUACAGAUGAGGAGGAGGAAGAUUUUCUCAACAAGCAACAUGUCAUCACACUACCGUGGUCAAAGAGUACUUAAAGAUUAUUUGUUCAUUACUGUUUCCAUUUUGUACCCAGAGUAAAGCAAACAACUGAGAAAAGUAACCAAGUGAUUACCUAUCCAAGUGCUGGAGAUUUUGAUUACUAAUGUCUUUGAUGUUUCAAGGCUACAAACUAAUAAAAGUAAAAUUAUAAGUUCAAGGGCUUAUUCUUCCAAUGAUAUAUUAUAUGUCAACCACUAAUCUAUAUUGCAGAUUAUGUUAGUAAAAUAUGGUGAAUUUGAAGAAAUAACUGUUACAACUGUGUCUAUAAAACCUACUAUAGGGCAGAACAUGAUUAUACUUAAAGAAAUAUUUCAUCGUCCAAUUAUAUUUUAAAUAAUUAUGUCAUCAACAAGAGUGUGCAUUUGACAGCCAAGUCACACUAGUUAGUAUCAUCAAUUGAACCUAUAAUUACACUGUUUAUUUUCUGGUUUUUAACAUUUAUAGAAGUUCUGGUAUCUUCAAAAAUUUGCAAUAAAAGAAAAAAAGAGGACCAAAAAUAAAAUGGGUGUGAAACUUUUCAUACUCUGCUCUAGCAAAACACAGUAAAGACCUCUAAGCAUCUUUUUUUAAGAAGGUCAAUGUAGUGAUUAGCUUUAUGUGAAAAUGUGACUGGUCUACAAUACCCAAAUGAUAUGGGUUGGCUCUGUCCCCACCCAGAUCUCAUCUUGAAUUGUAGUUUCUAUAAUCUCCAGGUGUCCUGGGAGGGACCUGGUGGGAAGUAAUUGAAUCAUGGGGGCAGUUACCCCUAUGCUGCUGUUCUCGUGAUAAUGAGUUCUCAUGUGAUCUGAUGGUUUUAUAAGGGGCUGUCCCCCCUUUUGCUCAGGACUUCUCUUUGCUGCUCCACUUGAAGAAGAAUGUGUUUGCUUCCCCUUUCACCAUGAUUUCCUGAGGCCUCCCCCACCAUGCUGAACUGUGAGUCAAUUAAACCUCUGUCCUUUAUAAAUUA